GCUGAUCCCAAAGGCGCGGCGGGGAGGGGAGCCGGGGCCCCAGCCCUGCCGGGAAACGGGUUCCCAGUCCCGGCCGAGAGCGCGGGCGCCGAGGGGACCGACCCGGACUCCCCGCAACCCCCCAACCGCCAGGCCAUGGCGCCCACGGGGCUCCUGGUGGCCGGCGCCUCCUUCCUCGCGUUCCGGGGGCUGCACUGGGGGUUGCGGCGGCUGCCCACGCCGGAAUCGGCCGCUCGGGACCGCUGGCAGUGGUGGAACCUCUGCGUCUCCCUGGCGCACAGCCUGCUCUCGGGGACCGGGGCGCUGCUCGGCCUGUCACUGUACCCUCAGAUGGCCGCCGACCCCAUCCAUGGCCACCCGCGCUGGGCUCUGGUGCUGGUGGCUGUGUCUGUGGGUUACUUCCUGGCAGACGGAGCUGACCUGCUGUGGAACCAGACCUUGGGCAAGACCUGGGAUCUUCUCUGUCAUCAUUUGGUGGUGGUGAGCUGCCUCAGCACCGCUGUUCUGUCUGGCCACUACGUGGGCUUCUCCAUGGUGUCUCUGCUCCUGGAACUGAACUCUGCCUGCUUGCACCUGCGGAAGCUGCUGUUGCUUUCUCGCCAGGCCCCAUCCCUGGCCUUCAGCGUGACCAGCUGGGCCUCCUUGGCCACCUUGGCCCUCUUCCGCCUGGUCCCGCUGGGGUGGAUGAGUCUGUGGCUGUUCCGGCAGCACCACCAGGUUCCUCUUGCUCUGGUCACCCUGGGUGGAAUUGGGCUGGUCACUGUGGGCAUCAUGAGCAUCAUAUUGGGGAUCCGUAUUCUGGUCAAUGAUGUCCUACAGUCUCGACCCCAUCCACCCAGCCCUGGCCAUGAGAAAACCAGGGGGACCAGGACACGUCGUGACAAUGGACCUGUCACCAGCAACAGUUCGACUCUCAGCCUGAAAGACUAGAGAGAAGCCAUGGGCCCCUCGCUGGGGGAGGUGGGGCCAGGACAAGGAGAUGAGGGUCUUCCAUGCACAGUCCCCCAUCAGGGUGAGGGCCAGACUUGCUCAUCAGAAUCUCAGUUUCUCUUCCAGCUAACUCACAUCCCUUCCCCUUCCUCGGAUCUAAGAAGAAAUGCUGAUGUUGGAUGGGUGGGAACCUGGGUUUCUGUUCACUGAAAUCCGUCAUCAGAUGAGCAUCCUUUCCAGCAAAUAAACUCAAGAGGUACAGCUAGAGCUAUCAGUAAAGGGUGGCAGGAGGCAUGCAGCUGGAAGAAACUGCCAGUGGAGACAGAAGCUCUUUGCUUUAACCCAGGGACAGAUGGGGGAAGGUGAAGUCCCACUAGGAUCAGAGAGAUCUGGUAUGGGGCGGGUGGGGACAGAGAGAAAAGAGAUCUCACCUAUAACCAAAUUCUGGCAGUGGGAGGAAGGUAGAGGAGGUGCUAUCUGUAGCAGCAGAGAUGGACGUGAUAGUUGCCAAGAGACAGAACCUGGGCCACAGCAAUUGCUGCUGAUGUUUCUGGUUCUCAAAGCCACACUCCUGUUUUUCUUUUUCUUUUUCUUUUUUUUUAUGAGACGGAAUCUUACUCUGUCACCCAGGCUGGAGUGUAGUGGCACGAUUUCGGCUCACUGCAACCUCAGCCUCCUGGGUUCAAGUGAUUGUCCUGCCUUAGCCUCCCGAGUAGCUGUGACUUCAGGCAUGCACCACCAAGCCCAGCUAAUUUUUGUAUUUUUUGGUGGAGAGGAGGUUUCACCAUGUUGCCCAGGCUGGUCUCGAACUCCUGACCUCAAGUAAUCCACCUGCCUCGGCCUCCCAGAGUGCUGGGAUUACAGACGUGAGAACAGGCGCACACUCCUGUUUUUCUCCUUAACCCUGGUCCUGCUGUGUCUAGCCUUUUAUUUUUAUUUUUAUUUUUAGUAUCUUUUGACUUUUCUUUUUUCUUUUCUUUUUUUUUUUUUUUUUUUGAGACAAGUUCUUGCUCUGUUGCCCAGGAUGGAGUGCAGUGGCUUGAUCUUGGCUCACUGCAAUCUCUGCCUCCCAGGCUCAAGCAAUUCUCCUGCCUCCCACCUCAGCCUCCCAAGUAGCUGGGACUACAGGUGCACGCCACUGCACCAGGCUAAUUUUUGUAUUUUUUUGUAGAGACCAGGUUUUGCCAUGUUGCCCAGGCUGGUCUCAAACUUUUGCACUCAAGUGAUCCACCCACCUCAGCCUCCCAAAGUGCUGGGAUUACAGACGUGAGCCACCGUACCCGACCCCUUUUGACUUUUCAAAGACAAUUCGGAUUCUUAGAGGAAUGAACACAGGGCUGGUUUGUCUUCUUAGGACGGCACUGAAGUCUAGAAUUACAGAAGGAAAGGUGCCCAGUACAGAGUUUUCCCAGGCCCAGGCUUUCAUGGAAGAACAAGGGCAGAGGUAGACUGUGUGAGAGAAGGCUGCAGGAGGAUAAAGGAAUAGCUGGCCCUCUGGCUGGGCGCAGCAGCUCACGCCUGUAAUCCCAGCACUUUGGGAGGCCGAGGCGGGAGGAUCACCUGAGGUCAGGAGUUCAAGACCAGCCUGGUCAACAUGGUGAAACCCUGUCUCUACUAAAAAUACAAAAUUAGCCGGGCAUGGUGGUGCAUGCCUGUAAUCCCAGCUACUCAGGAGGCUGAGGCAGGAGAAUCGCUUGAACCCAGGAGGCAGAGGUUGCAGUGAGCCGAGGUCGUGCCACUGCACUCCAGCCUGGGCAAACAGAGUGAGACUCUUGUCUCUAAAGAAAAAAAAAAAAGGAAGAGCUGGGACUUUUCUGAGAUACAUUCAUAAAGUCUUCUUCCUCCCUGCUGCUUCUGCUGCGUUUUUUUCUGUUGAACAAGACCCCUUCCUUCCCAGAACAUCGAGGUGACGGGAAGUGCCCAGCAGAUUAAGUCUGCUGUUCCACUAAACAAUGGACUGAGAGAGGCAACCCUUAGCCAUCCACAGAAAAGCUACAUGAGCAAAAGCAAGAGACAGGAAGAUUGUCUUCAAAAAAAAACAAAACAAAACAAAAACCUUGCUAAGAAGCGGAGGUACAGAAAGAUACGAAGAAUGACAGAGACAGACAUACAUAGAUUGAGUGAUAGAUAGAAAGAGAGAAGGAUUAUUCACAUAGAGGUGACAGAGGCAAAGAAGGAUGGAGGGCAAAAGAGACAGGCCCUAGCAGAAAUAUGGAGAAAGGCUGUCAUAGAUCCUGAGAGACACCAAAGUCACAGAACUGAUAAAAGGGUUAUAAACAAAAAGGACCAGAAAAAUAGAAAUGAAGGCCGACAAGAAGAGACCCCAAGGCUGAAAGGCACAGAGAGUCUAGACAGUGAAAUAGAGUGAGUGACAAGGAGAAACACCCAGGCUCAGGAGUGAUGGAGGAAAUACUGGCAGAUAGAGAGAUCAGAAGAGCAAGAGGAGAGGUGGGAACAGAGAAGAGCGGGGACGAGUCCGGGGAGCUGAGAAGCAGAAGGCGGAGGAGGCAGUCAGUGGGAAGAUUCACUGACAGAAGAGACCAGGAGAUAUGGGGACUUGGAGGCAGGCAGAAAGACAAAGGACAAACAGCUGCAGCGCAAACCCUAAAGACAGGCUGACAGUAACCGGUCGGCAGAGACUGGUAGGAAGAUAAGGACAAGUCAGAAUCAGGGGUGUCAACUGAGAUGCAAAUAUAGGCAAAGGAGCUGACAAAGAGAAUCACAGAGAGAAAAAAAAGGAGGAGAGCACAGAACAAUUUAAAUAUCCAGGCUGGGCAUGGUGGGUCACGCCUGUAAUCCCAGCAUUUUGGGAGGCCGAGGCAGGCGGAUCACGAGGUCAGGAGAUGACCAUCCUGGCUAACAUGGUGAAACACCAUCUCUACUAAAAAUACAAAAAAUUGGCCGGGCGUGGUGGCAGGCGCCCGUAAUCCCGGCUACUGAGGAGGCUGAGGCAGGAGAAUCGUUUGAACCUGGGAGGCCGAGGUUGUUAUAAUGAGCCGAGAUAGUGCCACUGCAGUCCAGCAGGGGUGACAGAGUGAGACUCCGUCUCAAAAAAAAAAAUUGAAUAUCCAAAGAACAAAGAAGAGGCAGGAACCCAGAAAUGAAAAGAGGAGGAAAAAUACAGGUGUGAAAAAAAAAUGAGAGGGAUUGUGAGAAGUCUCCAUCAUAGAGUCAUAAAAACAGGCGCAAAGGAUGAAAAUACAUCGAGACUGAGGAAAACACAGUUGGAAGGAGCUAAACACAAGCAGAAAAUAAGAGCAGAGCAUUUAAAUGUAAUUAGAUAAAAACCCAAGAGGCAAAGGUAUAGAUAGUGAGCUAGAGAAACAAUGCAGAAUUUUGUCAGAGUCUGUACUUCUAGAAGUCAUGUUUGCUGGCUGGGCAUGGUGGCUCACGCCUGUAAUCCCAGCACUUUGGGAGGCCGAGGUAGGAGGAGUGGUUGAGCUCAGGAGUUCAAGACCAGUCUGGGCAACAUAUUGAGACCUCCUCUCUACAAAAAAAAAAAAUUUUCUUUUUUCUUUCUUUUCUUCUUUUUUUUUUUUUUUUUUUGAGACAGUUUCAUUCUUGCUGCCCAGGCUGGAAUGCAGUGGCACAAUCUUGGCUCACUGCAACCUCCACCUCCUGGACUCAAGUGAUUCUCCUGCCUCAGCCUCCCUAGUAGCUGGGAUUACAGGUACCCACCACCACACUCGGCUAAUUUUUGUGUUUUUAGUAGAGACAGGAUUUCACCAUAUUGGCCAGGCUGGUCUCAAACUCCUGACCUCAGGUGAUCCGCCCACCUUGGGCUCCCAAACUACUGGGAUUAUAUGCGUGAGCCAACACACCCGGCCAAAAAAAAAUUUUUAAUUAAAAAAAAAAGUCAUAUCUGCAAAACUCAAUUUGCCAUCUUAACUGAAUGCCUUGAUUAACAAAAAUGUUGUCUGCCUUGAGUUUUUAAAGAAAAAGAAAUAUGACAAACUCAUGUGAGGAAUCUAUUCCUUAAAUAUCUGUUGAGGUUGAUAUGAAUUGAUUCUAAGUCAUACACCUUUUCUUUGGCCACUGGUAUACAUUCAUGAUGGUUUGAGUGAGUGUCCCUUUUGGUAAUACUUGAUAGUGUCUAUGAGGCCGGGCGUGGUGGCUCACGCCUGUAAUCCCAGCACUUUGGGGGACCGAGGCAGGUGAAAUCCCAUCUCUACUAAAAAUAAAAAAAAUUAGCCGGGCGUGGUGGCGGGCGCCUGUAGUCCCAGCUACUCAGGAGGCUGAGGCAGGAGAAUGGCAUGAACCCGGGAGGCGGAGCUUGCAGUGAGCCAAGAUCGUGCCACUGCACUCCAGCCUGGGUGACAGAGCAAGACUCCGUCUUAAAAAAUAAAUAAAUAAAUAAAUAGACAGAUAGAUAGAUAGAUAGUGUCUAUGAAGGCUGCCCAAGAACUUGACCAUUAGGGAAACAUGGCUGUUUCUGUGGAUUAACUAGUCAAGCCCAUACAGGAAGAGUGAGGUCAGCUCCCAGGUGGGGCAGGAUGUAGUGGACGCUUGGAAGAAUUUGGGACCACACACGAAUUGCUACCAUGGUGAGCCAGUGAAACUUGAGGAAGGCAGGACUGGAUUGUGAUUACAACUGAGUAAGUAGGCAGAGAAUUGGAGUGUGGGCAACAUAAAGAUGAUGUGAAUCAAAGAAGAAUGGUCAAUUAAGACCCUAAAAAAAGGACGUUCAAAAAUGCAGAGGUUAAAAAAAAAAAAAGCAGAGAUUGCCAGAUGCUCCAUUUGGUAGGAGUCUGCUUAGCACAGUGGUGCUUCGCCAGACUUUACCGUGGCCCAGGGAAAUGGUCCUCAAGACGGACUCCAUGUCUACCAAGCUACUUGCUAAUGAUUUCUUUGUCCUCCAGGACAGGGAAGGGGCUUUUCUGGAUGGGAUACAUUGAUAUUUUAUGGCCUUGAAACACUAUCCUGAUUAUAAAUUAAUAAAUUGCUAUGCAAAUAA